GCAAUUGUGCCCUGGUUCGCCAAGAUGUCGUUCCCAAAGUAUAAGCCGUCGAGCCUGCGCACUCUGCCUGAGACCCUCGACCCAGCCGAAUACAACAUAUCUCCGGAAACCCGGCGGGCGCAAGCCGAGCGGUUGGCCAUAAGAGCCCAGCUGAAACGAGAGUACCUGCUUCAGUACAACGAUCCCAACCGCCGAGGGCUCAUCGAAAAUCCUGCCUUGCUUCGUUGGGCCUAUGCAAGAACAAUAAAUGUCUAUCCUAAUUUCAGACCCACUCCUAAAAACUCACUCAUGGGAGCUCUGUGUGGAUUUGGGCCCCUCAUCUUCAUUUAUUAUAUUAUCAAAACUGAGAGGGUAAGUAUUCAGACCAGAUGUUUAGUAUUUGAGUGAUAGGUUCACUUUCUAGGGACCAGCUGCAGCUCCUUCUCUUGAAGAUUGCCACCAGUGCCCCUCCCACCUUGGGGCUGUCCUCUGCCUUCCCUUCCUCUCUUCUUUUAUCUUUAUUCCUUUCCAGCAGGAGUUAAAACAGAAAGUUUUCAGUCACCUUUGUCUAUUUUUGUUAGUUCAUUUGUUUUUUAAAAAGAUGAUGUUUAUUGGGUUAAGUAUUAGCAGAAUACAUAAAUCAUUUAGUACGUUUCCUGUUUGCGUGAAUUCUAUUUAUGUUGGUCACAUUUUGCAAAUUAAUGUUAAAACCUAUUAAUACUCUACGGACAGAGAAGCACAAGCUGCCUGUGUGGGGAAUAGCUGCCGUCAGCAGCCUGGGUAUAUGAUUGGAGAGAAAGUCAAGCUGAUCUUUGGCACCAAACCAUUCCACAUCUGGUACUAAACCCUGAGCUGCAGCCCCCAGGCUUGUGUUGCCACUGGAGCCCACUCGUCUAGCUUUGUCUUUAACUGGCCCAUCUGCAUUCCCAUUAGAGUUCGUGUAUUUUGAUUAUCUGGUGAAUGAUCUACUUAACAGAAAGGUAGUCCACAUUUUCCCAGAAAGUGUUUGCAUUUUGCUUUCAAUAUAUGGUUUUAUGGGAUAAUAUAUUUCUAAUGACUAAAAUGUGAGUAAGAUGUUUUUGAAUAGGAGCAUUUUCUUACUGUGUCUUUAGUUCCUCGGAUUACUGUUUCUUCGCACACUCCCUGGGCUUUAGACAGUGGGAUUGCAAUUAGGUUUGGAGUGUUUCAUUCUGUUUGUCAGUUGUACGGUGGGUUGUGCCAAAAUGCAGUUUUUCUUACCUUUUUUAUUUAUUUAUUUUUAUCUAAUAUAGCCAACUGGCAGAAUAUAUUGUCUUUAAUGUACUUUUUUUCUGUCUUUACAGGAUAGGAAAGAAAAACUUAUCCAGGAAGGAAAAUUGGAUCGAACAUUUCACCUCUCAUAUUAAGUCUGGCAAUGAUGACUAUAUGUAUUCCUGCCUAAAUAAAUCAUCUAUUAAUCAUUAAGUAGUAGUUUCUCUUUCUUAGUAUUACCUUGAUUCAAUGUUAAAAACUAUUAACACCCUAACAACACAGAAGCAGACGCAGCC